AUUCAGGAGGAGUAACUGGAAGCCAUAACCAUGAACUUCCAUAUCUGUCAUAGGAAAGAGGUUGGCCUCAGCAGCAAUGAGGGAUAAUUCUUUCAAGAAAGGAAUGAAGAGAGAAGUUAGAUGGAAAAGAGAUUUUUAAGGUCAAAAGAAGCAGCUGAAGAACAUGUGUAGGACAGCCUUAGGAGUUACUACACUUCAAGACCUGGGUGUCUGCUGGAGGAAGGAACAUGACCCUGCGGAGAUGUUAAGGGUUGGGAGAGCUGAGCUUGGAGGCUGGAAGCCCAGCUGGGAGGCUAUUGUUAAAGAGGUUGCUGCAGCAACUGGUCACACAGUAGUGUUGGUAGACCAGACAGAGGACAUCCUGGCAAAAUCCAAAAAGGGAAUUGAGGAAAGCCUUAGGAAAGUGGCAAAGAAGAAGUUUGCAGAAAACCUUAAGGCCGGCGAUGAAUUUGUGGAGAAGACCCUGAGCACCAUAGCGACCAGCACGGAUGCAGCCUCCGUUGUCCACAGCACAGACUUGGUGGUGGAAGCCAUCGUGGAGAAUCUGAAGGUGAAAAACGAGCUCUUCAAAAGGCUGGACAAGUUUGCUGCUGAACAUACAAUCUUUGCCAGCAACACUUCCUCCUUGCAGAUUACAAGCAUAGCUAAUGCCACCACCAGACAAGACCGAUUCGCUGGCCUCCAUUUCUUCAACCCAGUGCCUGUCAUGAAACUUGUGGAGGUCAUUAAAACACCAAUGACCAGCCAGAAGACAUUUGAAUCUUUGGUAGACUUUAGCAAAGCCCUAGGAAAGCAUCCUGUUUCUUGCAAGGACACUCCUGGGUUUAUUGUGAACCGCCUCCUGGUUCCAUACCUCAUGGAAGCAAUCAGGCUGUAUGAACGAGGUGACGCAUCCAAAGAAGACAUUGACACUGCUAUGAAAUUAGGAGCCGGUUACCCCAUGGGCCCAUUUGAGCUUCUAGAUUAUGUCGGACUGGAUACUACGAAGUUCAUCGUGGAUGGGUGGCAUGAAAUGGAUGCAGAGAACCCAUUACAUCAGCCCAGCCCAUCCUUAAAUAAGCUGGUAGCAGAGAACAAGUUCGGCAAGAAGACUGGAGAAGGAUUUUACAAAUACAAGUGAUGUGCAGCUUCUCCGGCUCUGAGAAGAACACCUGAGAGCGCUUUCCAGCCAGUGCCCCGAGUGCCUGUGGGAAUGCUCUUUGGUCAGACAUUCCCUCACACAGUACAGUUUAAUAAAUGUGCAUUUUGAUUGUAAUCUAUCGAAGUGAUUAUUACACCAGUUACAGCAGUAAUAGAUUCUCCAUUAAGAAAUAAUUCCCUUUUUUAGUCUGUUCAUUUCUGUGUAUUUUCUAAACAGCUUUACACCCUUGGUGCCUUGGAGCAAACAUGUUUUUUGAACCUUGUCAUUUUUGUGAAGAAUUGCCUAGAUUCCUUCUCUCAUCAACGGGAAAGUACUUCCUCUGAGAGUGCGAGUGCACCAUGCUCACUGUUGCUGCGUGGGAGAGUCACAAGCCACUGGCAAGCAAGUGGUAUAGUCUGUGAAGCACUGCAGCGAGCAGCACCUGGAUCUUGCCUUUAUAAGAACAUUUUACUACCUGCAGCUUUGAGUCUUGCCCUACAUUUUGGGCAUGACAUAAGAUGUGUCUUUAUUCAGCUCGUCGUGAAGAUGCUGCUGCUGAAUGGGUCAGCAUAUCUCUGUUUGCAUGGUUUGCAGGAGGUCGGUUUUCAUGGUCAUUCAGUUCCACAGAUCUGAAUGAUUACUGUCUGUCUGUGUCUUUUUUCCAUGAGAAAUCACUGUUGCAAAUUGCCUAUAAAUUGACUCUACUAAAAUAACAAUGUUUCAGUCUGAAAAUUUGAAUUGAAAAAAAUGUAUAAUAUAAAAUUGUAAUACACUCAAAUGAUUAUAAAAGUAAAAGUUGGUAAUUUAGGCAGAA